AGAGAGCCCCGGAGCCGCGGCGGGAGAGGAACGCGCAGCCAGCCUUGGGAAGCCCAGGCCCGGCAGCCAUGGCGGUGGAAGGAGGAAUGAAAUGUGUGAAGUUCUUGCUCUACGUCCUCCUGCUGGCCUUUUGCGCCUGUGCAGUGGGACUGAUUGCCGUGGGUGUCGGGGCACAGCUUGUCCUGAGUCAGACCAUAAUCCAGGGGGCUACCCCUGGCUCUCUGUUGCCAGUGGUCAUCAUCGCAGUGGGUGUCUUCCUCUUCCUGGUGGCUUUUGUGGGCUGCUGCGGGGCCUGCAAGGAGAACUAUUGUCUUAUGAUCACGUUUGCCAUCUUUCUGUCUCUUAUCAUGUUGGUGGAGGUGGCCGCAGCCAUUGCUGGCUAUGUGUUUAGAGAUAAGGUGAUGUCAGAGUUUAAUAACAACUUCCGGCAGCAGAUGGAGAAUUACCCGAAAAACAACCACACUGCUUCGAUCCUGGACAGGAUGCAGGCAGAUUUUAAGUGCUGUGGGGCUGCUAACUACACAGAUUGGGAGAAAAUCCCUUCCAUGUCGAAGAACCGAGUCCCCGACUCCUGCUGCAUUAAUGUUACUGUGGGCUGUGGGAUUAAUUUCAACGAGAAGGCGAUCCAUAAGGAGGGCUGUGUGGAGAAGAUUGGGGGCUGGCUGAGGAAAAAUGUGCUGGUGGUAGCUGCAGCAGCCCUUGGAAUUGCUUUUGUCGAGGUUUUGGGAAUUGUCUUUGCCUGCUGCCUCGUGAAGAGUAUCAGAAGUGGCUACGAGGUGAUGUAGGGGUCUGGUCUCCUCAGCCUCCUCAUCUGGGGGAGUGGAAUAUGUCCUUAGCAGGAGAAUUUAUGUGAAUAUUGCCUUUUCUUCCAUGGAAGCCACCCAGCCUGGCCCAGAACCCUCAUCACCUGCUCUUCUCCCCCAAGAAAUAUGAAGACCAUUCCCAGUACAGACACUGAAUUGCAACCUUACUCCCCUUCAGAAAAUAAGGGAAAUGUAUUAAAGUGCCCUUUGAUGGCCACUCCCCGACGUGCAGCUGUAGAUGUGAGGCAGUUCCCUGGCGCCCCACUGUGGGUGCUAGCUGUUUUGCAGGGACUGAACAGGCCAGAGACCGUGAGCAUGUCGGUUUGGAGUAGUUGGCACUUAAAUGGGGUCAGCCUUCCACUGGGCACAUUUCUGCCCACCUUCUUUUUAUUUUUUAAACAAUACACUUUUGUUAGUGCUUAUUUUGUGGCAGGCACCAGGCAGUACCAGGGUGGGGGCAGAAAUAAAUCAAAGUCCUUGUCCUUGAAAAACAAUCUCUUGCUGGAAGGCUGGAUUCAGUAGACUGCUUGGGCAGGCUUGGGAAGGACCCAGGUGAGCACAGCAUCCACCAGGCUGGCUGGCAGGUAGGAGGCAGGCAGCCAGAGCAGCUUGGCAUCCCAACCUGGGCUGUAGCGGGUUCGGGGGUGUCGAGCAGUCAGGGCAUGCUCCAGGCAUCGGCUCACCUUGGUUAGGUCCGGGUCACAGAUCAGGUUCAUGAUGCGCUGUUGCAUUUUCAGGUCUGCAGCCCCAUAGGUGGUUGCAAUCAGUUUCCCUUCCUCACUCCAGCCCAUCUUAGGUACUGUCUUCUGGGGCCCUGGGCUUGUCACCCUCAGUCCCCUCCUCAGUGUGGGGAGUGGGCAGGUUCCACAUGGCCUGGGCACUCUUGUAACAUCCUGUUCACCCUCAACCCUGCCCUGGGUGCCCCACCCACCUCCUAGCAGGCUUAUGCAGGACUGGCCUUUCUGGUACUUGUUUCCCUUCAUGUGCCCCUGUGUGGGCCUGGCUACUCACACUUGGUGAGGAAGGCCCCCCCAUAGUGGGCCUGUGUGGCAGGAGGCAGCCGUGCCCAGCAGGCCUGCAGGGUUUUCUCCAGACUCUCCAGGUUGGUCACAGGGGUUCGGAAGAAGCCAGGCUCCACGAUGGAGACUCGUAUCCCAAAAUGAGCUACAUCCCGCCUAGAGUCGGGGCAGAGCGAAGUUGCUGGGUUCUUGCCCUAUAGGGAGGGGACUUUGAGGGACAUGGGUUGGGGAGCUGAGAAAGUUACCACAGACCAGGGACAAGAGUUUUGACGGAGAUGCCUACUGCCCCGGGACAAGGGUCAAGUGGGGUAGAGGGAGGAAAGUAUUUUUGAGGUUUGUUUUCUUUGAUCUAGAGCAGGGGUCAGCACGUUUUUUUCUUAAAGGGCCAGAGAGUUAAUAUUUUAAGCAUGGCAGGCCAAGAAACAAAAUUAAUGAUAUUAUCAGGUACUUAUAUAACAGUUUACAAUGUAACCAUUUAAAAAUAAAAAAAACCAUUAUCAGCUUGUA